GUAGCUGAUCCCAGCCUAACCUGGCCCGGCUGGCUGCUGGUGGGAGGCCGGCGACUGAGUAAGAUGAAGAUCCAGUUUCAGACAUGAGACUCGUUGGGUGAUCAUUUCAUUGAGAUCAACCUGAAUGACCAGGUGUAAAGUGCAAGAGUAAUAUGCUAUGACUGAGGCAACUCAAAUUUUUUAAUUGCCAAUUUCUGUUUCUUUUGAUUCUACAAAAGUAACUAUGUUUCCGGUAGCCCCUAAACCCCAGGAUUCCAGUCAACCAUCAGACAGACUCAUGACUGAAAAACAGCAGGAAGAAGCAGAAUGGGAAAGCAUAAAUGUGCUAUUGAUGAUGCAUGGCUUAAAACCUUUGUCUCUAGUCAAAAGAACAGAUCUCAAAGAUCUCAUCAUUUUUGACAAACAGUCAUCACAAAGGAUGAGACAGAAUUUGAAAUUGUUGGUGGAAGAAACAUCAUGUCAACAGAACAUGAUACAGGAGCUUAUAGAAACUAAUCAACAGCUUAGAAAUGAACUUCAGCUAGAGCAAAGCCGAGCAGCCAAUCAAGAACAACGAGCUAAUGACUUGGAACAAAUUAUGGAAAGUGUGAAAUCCAAAAUUGGUGAAUUGGAGGAUGAAUCACUAAGUAGGGCUUGCCACCAACAGAAUAAAAUAAAAGAUCUUCAAAAGGAGCAGAAAACUUUACAGGUGAAGUGCCAGCAUUAUAAGAAAAAACGAACGGAGCAAGAAGAAACUAUUGCUUCUUUGCAAAUGGAAGUCUGUAGAUUAAAAAAGGAGGAAGAAGAUCGCAUUGUCACUCAAAACAGAGUGUUUGCCUAUCUGUGCAAAAGAGUUCCUCAUACCGUCUUGGAUAGACAGUUGCUUUGUCUAAUUGAUUACUAUGAAUCUAAAAUUAGAAAAAUUCAUACACAAAGGCAAUAUAAAGAAGAUGAAAGUCAGUCAGAAGAAGAAAACGACUACAGAAAUCUGGAUGCCUCACCAACUUAUAAAGGCCUUUUAAUGUCAUUACAGAAUCAACUCAAGGAAUCAAAAUCUAAGAUUGAUGCACUUUCAAGUGAAAAGCUGAACCUCCAAAAAGAUUUGGAAACCAGGCCUACGCAGCAUGAAUUAAGACUUUAUAAACAGCAGGUGAAGAAGCUGGAAAAAGCCCUUAAGAAAAACGUCAAAUUACAGGAGCUUAUUAAUCAUAAGAAGGCUGAGGACACAGAGAAGAAAGAUGAGCCCAGCAAAUAUAAUCAGCAACAGGCCCUAAUUGACCAGAGAUACUUUCAGGUGCUGUGUAGCAUCAAUUCAAUUAUCCACAAUCCAAGAGCUCCAGUAAUAAUUUAUAAACAGACCAAAGGGGGAGUCCAAAAUUUUAAUAAAGAUCUUGUUCAAGAUUGUGGAUUUGAGCAUCUUGUUCCUGUAAUAGAAAUGUGGGCAGAUCAACUGACAUCCUUAAAGGAAAUGAGUGACAUAAAAAUAGAUUACCGGUUGAAGUUCUGAGUGAAUGAUGCAGAUAACUUGUGCUCUAGAGUCUGGAGGAGAAAGAGAACACUCUGAUUGUAGCCCCCAAGAAGGGCUUUGCCAUGGUGGUGAGUUCUUGCUAUUGUAUGGUUUUCUGAGGAGGAGGAGGAGGCAAGGAAUUCGCUUUAUAAUUAGAAUAUUCUGAGGACACCCAAGAAGAAAUUAUUAAGAAUUAGUUACUUCUGCCAUUGGAGUAACUCAUGGAUUUUGAGCAGUGCUUCAGAUAUUAAUACUACAGUUUCAGGGUCCAAAUUAAGAAACUACAUGAGAUUCUCUGAGGCCUCAUAUCAAAGGUUAUUUGAUAUGUAGCAACCUCUAAGUUUGGGACAACCAUCUUCCCAGAUUAGUUUUUUCCCUCAGGUUAAAUUUGGCUUUAAAGAGUAAGAUAGGUUUGAGGGAUGAAUGGAUAAGCAAAAUGUGGUAUAUACAUAUAUUGCAAUAUUAUUCAGCCAUUAAAAGGAAAGAAAUUCUGACCCUUGCAACAUGGGUGAACAUUAUGAGGACAUUAUGCUAAGUGAAAUAAGUCAGUCACAAGAAGAUUCCACUUAUAUGAUUCCACUUGUAUGAGAUACUUAGUGAAAAUCAUAGAGACAAAGUAGAGUGGUGAUGGCUAGAGGGAGGAGGGAAAUGGGAAGUUAUUGUUUAAUGGGUAUAAAGUUUCAGUGUUACAAGAUGAAAAGAAUUAUGGAGAUGGAUGGUGAUGUUGGUUGCACAACAUUAUGAACAUAUUAACACUGAACUUACAUUUAAAAAUUGUUAAGAUGGUGAAUUUUAUGGGUAUUUUACUAGUUUUAAAAAUUGGAAGAAAAGAAGGCUGGGAAAGACAUGGAGCCAGCUGCCUCCAGCCUUGUGUCUUUUCCCUCCUGCCUUUCCAAGAAAGGUGAACUACAGAUGUUGUAGCUUUCCCCAACCCAGUACACUCUUGAAUACUUUUGCUUUGCUAUUCUCCAGUGCUUCAGAGGCCAGACGUACACGGUAGGCUGGCUCAUGGUAGUACUUCUACAUCUCCACAACUGGGCAAUGUAAAGAACCUAGGAGACCCUCUUAUAUUUUUCAGAGCUUACUUGAUGGACUGUGCUACAACCAUCCUGUCACUGCUUAGGAGACCAGAACAUCUUUUCUUCUUAGCUUUGUAAUACUCUUUUAUUCUGAAGCAAAAAUGUAUUAGAUUGGGUAUGCUUUUUACCAUAGAUUACUUUAUAAAUGUGCCUUGUUCCUGGAGCAUUGGUUAAUAAAGGUAUCAUUAUGCUGUUACUUGCUGACUUUUUUUUUUUUCAAAUUCUAGUGGCAUUGAUUGUAAAACAUUCAUUUGACAUGGAAUUUAUUGCUAUGAAUUACUAAAAUAGUAACUGCCUUCCUACCAAUUGAAAGGUUAAAGAUACCAAUAUGUGAAGUCUGAGCCUUAAGUGGAGAGUGUCAAGUGAAGUACUAAAAUAAGUUAGAAAAAGGAGGAACUUCUUGUACUUCUUUCUGUUCUCUAGAGCUGUGCUGUCUAGUAUGGUAGCCUCUAGCUGCAUGUGGUUAUUGAUCACUUGAAAGGUGGCUAGUCCUAAUUCAGAUGUGUUAUAAGUGUAAAAUAUACACUGGAUUUAGAAGACUUUGUAUGGGAAAAAUUAAAAUAAUUGAUUUUAUAUUGAAAUGAUAAUAUUUUGGAUAUAUUGGGUUAAAUAAAAUAUACUAGUACAGUUAAUAUCACAUGUUUCUUUUCACUUUCCAUACUAUGGCCCUAGACAACUUAAAAUUACUGUGGCUCACAUUACAUUUCUUUUGGACAGCGUUGUUCUAAAGGACCAAGCGCUGUGCCAUACACAUAUGGAUUGAGUAUCCCUUAUCCACAGUGCUUGGGCCUAGAAGUAUUUUGAUUAAGAAUUUUUUCAGAUUUUGGAGUAUUUGCAGAAUAUAUGCCAUUUGAGCAUCACUGAUCCAAAAAUCCGAAAUUCAGAAUGCUCCAAUGAGCAUUUCUUUUGAGUGUCCUGUUGUUGCUCAGAGUUUCAGAUUUUGGAGCAUUUCAGAUUUUCGGACUAGGAAUUCUAAAUAUUUGUCGAUUGAUCAGUCUAGAGCUCUAAACUUUCAGUAGCCUUGCCCAUUGUGCACAGUUUAAAAUCAAUUAGGGCACCACAACUAGGCCAAGAAAACUAAGUGGAGUAUUAUAAUGUAGAAUACAUUUAGGGAACCUUUCACAUUAAAAACUUGCCUGGAGAUACAUGUUAUAACAUGGAUAAAUCUUAAAAACAUUAUGCUAAGUGAGAGACGUCAUUCAUAAAAGACUACUUAUUGUAUAAUUCCCUUUAUGCAAAAUGCCUAGAAUAGGCAAAUCCAUAGAAACAGAAAAUAGUUUAGAGAUUAACCCUAGGAGCUGCAGGGAAGGGAAAAUGGGGAAGGAAGGACUCUUAGUGGGUCUGAGAUUUCUUUUUGGAGUAAUGAAUAUGUUCUGAAAUUGGAUAGUGCUGAUGUUUGUACAUGUGUGAAAAUAUUAAAACUACUGAAUUGUAUACUUAGGGUAAAUUUUAUGGUAUAUGAAUUACAUCUCAAUAAAGCUGUUAUAUAACAUAUUCAAAACCAAAA